AUACCAGCUCUGAGAUUUCCAGCUCAGCGAUGCCCCCAGGUCCCUGGGAGAGCUGCUUCUGGGUGGGGGGCCUCAUUUUGUGGCUCAGCGUUGGAAGUUCAGAAAAUUAACCUGCUCUACUUUGGGUUCUCAGAAGUUCUCAGAAGACUCCUUCUCACUAUGGGGAUGCACCUCCUACCCCACAGCCAAAGUGCGCUGACUUCCAGAGCGCCAACCUUUUUGAAGGCACCGAUCUCAAAGUCCAGUUUCUCCUCUUUGUCCCUUCGAAUCCUAGCUGUGGGCAGCUAGUAGAAGGAAGCAGUGACCUCCAAAACUCUGGGUUCAAUGCCACUCUGGGAACCAAACUAAUUAUCCAUGGAUUCAGGGUUUUAGGAACAAAGCCUUCCUGGAUUGACACAUUUAUUAGAACCCUUCUGCGUGCAACGAAUGCUAAUGUGAUUGCCGUGGACUGGAUUUAUGGGUCUACAGGAGUCUACUUCUCAGCUGUGAAAAAUGUGAUUAAGUUGAGCCUCGAGAUCUCCCUUUUCCUCAAUAAACUCCUGGUGCUGGGUGUGUCGGAAUCCUCAAUCCACAUCAUUGGUGUUAGCCUGGGGGCCCACGUUGGGGGCAUGGUGGGACAGCUCUUCGGAGGCCAGCUGGGACAGAUCACAGGCCUGGACCCCGCUGGACCUGAGUACACCAGGGCCAGUGUGGAAGAGCGCUUGGAUGCUGGAGAUGCCCUCUUCGUGGAAGCCAUCCACACAGACACCGACAAUUUGGGUAUUCGGAUUCCCGUUGGACAUGUGGACUACUUCGUCAACGGAGGCCAAGACCAACCUGGCUGCCCCACCUUCUUUUACGCAGGUUAUAGUUAUCUGAUCUGUGAUCACAUGAGGGCUGUGCACCUCUACAUCAGCGCCCUGGAGAAUUCCUGUCCACUGAUGGCCUUUCCCUGUGCCAGCUACAAGGCCUUCCUUGCUGGACGCUGUCUGGAUUGCUUUAACCCUUUUCUGCUUUCCUGCCCAAGGAUAGGACUGGUGGAACAAGGUGGUGUCAAGAUAGAGCCGCUCCCCAAGGAAGUGAAAGUCUACCUCCUGACUACUUCCAGUGCUCCGUACUGCAUGCAUCACAGCCUCGUGGAGUUUCACUUGAAGGAACUGAGAAACAAGGACACCAACAUCGAGGUUACCUUCCUUAGCAGUAACAUCACCUCUUCAUCUAAGAUCACCAUACCUAAGCAGCAACGCUAUGGGAAAGGAAUCAUAGCCCAUGCCACCCCACAAUGCCAGAUAAACCAAGUGAAAUUCAAGUUUCAGUCUUCCAACCGAGUUUGGAAAAAAGACCGGACUACCAUUAUUGGGAAGUUCUGCACUGCCCUUUUGCCUGUCAAUGACAGAGAAAAGAUGGUCUGCUUACCUGAACCAGUGAACUUACAAGCAAGUGUGACUGUUUCCUGUGACCUGAAGAUAGCCUGUGUGUAGUUUAACCUGGGCAGGACACAUCUCCCUGCAUUUUUUUUUUUUUUUUGAGAGAGAGGUGUGAUGAGGGAUGUGUGUGUGCAGCUUAUUGUAGACCAUUACUACUAAGGAGAAAAGCAAAGCUCUUUCUUAUUUUCCUCAUAAUCAGCUACCCUGGAGGGGAGGGAGAACUCAUUUUACAGAACUUGGUUUCCUUUGCCGAUCUUAUGUACAUACCCAUUUUAGCUUUCCCAUGCAUACUUAACUGCACUUGCUUUAUCUCCUUGGGCAUUCGUACUUAGGAUUCAAUAGAAACAUGUACAGGGUAAACAAUUUUUUAAAAAUAAAACUUCAUGGAGUAUCUGAA